GCAACCCACACCGCCCCUGCCAGCCACCAUGGGGCUGCCACUAGCCCGCCUGGCGGCUGUGUGCCUGGCCCUGUCUUUGGCAGGGGGCUCGGAGCUCCAGACAGAGGGCAGAACCCGAAACCACGGCCACAACGUCUGCAGCACCUGGGGCAACUUCCACUACAAGACCUUCGACGGGGACGUCUUCCGCUUCCCCGGCCCCUGCGACUACAACUUCGCCUCCGACUGCCGAGGCUCCUACAAGGAAUUUGCUGUGCACCUGAAGCGGGGUCCGGGCCAGGCUGAGGCCCCCGCCGGGGUGGAGUCCAUCCUGCUGACCAUCAAGGAUGACACCAUCUACCUCACCCGCCACCUGGCUGUGCUUAACGGGGCCGUGGUCAGCACCCCGCACUACAGCCCCGGGCUGCUCAUUGAGAAGAGCGAUGCCUACACCAAAGUCUACUCCCGCGCCGGCCUCACCCUCAUGUGGAACCGGGAGGAUGCACUCAUGCUGGAGCUGGACACUAAGUUCCGGAACCACACCUGUGGCCUCUGCGGGGACUACAACGGCCUGCAGAGCUAUUCAGAAUUCCUCUCUGACGGCGUGCUCUUCAGUCCCCUGGAGUUUGGGAACAUGCAGAAGAUCAACCAGCCCGAUGUGGUGUGUGAGGAUCCCGAGGAGGAGGUGGCCCCCGCAUCCUGCUCCGAGCACCGCGCCGAGUGUGAGAGGCUGCUGACCGCCGAGGCCUUCGCGGACUGUCAGGACCUGGUGCCGCUGGAGCCGUAUCUGCGCGCCUGCCAGCAGGACCGCUGCCGGUGCCCGGGCGGUGACACCUGCGUCUGCAGCACCGUGGCCGAGUUCUCCCGCCAGUGCUCCCACGCCGGCGGCCGGCCCGGGAACUGGAGGACCGCCACGCUCUGCCCCAAGACCUGCCCCGGGAACCUGGUGUACCUGGAGAGCGGCUCGCCCUGCAUGGACACCUGCUCACACCUGGAGGUGAGCAGCCUGUGCGAGGAGCACCGCAUGGACGGCUGUUUCUGCCCAGAAGGCACCGUAUAUGACGACAUCGGGGACAGUGGCUGCGUUCCUGUGAGCCAGUGCCACUGCAGGCUGCACGGACACCUGUACACACCGGGCCAGGAGAUCACCAAUGACUGCGAGCAGUGUGUCUGUAACGCUGGCCGCUGGGUGUGCAAAGACCUGCCCUGCCCCGGCACCUGUGCCCUGGAAGGCGGCUCCCACAUCACCACCUUCGAUGGGAAGACGUACACCUUCCACGGGGACUGCUACUAUGUCCUGGCCAAGGGUGACCACAACGAUUCCUACGCUCUCCUGGGCGAGCUGGCCCCCUGUGGCUCCACAGACAAGCAGACCUGCCUGAAGACGGUGGUGCUGCUGGCUGACAAGAAGAAGAAUGUGGUGGUCUUCAAGUCCGAUGGCAGUGUACUGCUCAACGAGCUGCAGGUGAACCUGCCCCACGUGACCGCGAGCUUCUCUGUCUUCCGCCCGUCUUCCUACCACAUCAUGGUGAGCAUGGCCAUUGGCGUCCGGCUGCAGGUGCAGCUGGCCCCAGUCAUGCAACUCUUUGUGACACUGGACCAGGCCUCCCAGGGGCAGGUGCAGGGCCUCUGCGGGAACUUCAACGGCCUGGAAGGUGACGACUUCAAGACGGCCAGCGGGCUGGUGGAGGCCACGGGGGCCGGCUUUGCCAACACCUGGAAGGCACAGUCAACCUGCCAUGACAAGCUGGACUGGUUGGACGAUCCCUGCUCCCUGAACAUCGAGAGCGCCAACUACGCCGAGCACUGGUGCUCCCUCCUGAAGAAGACAGAGACCCCCUUUGGCAGGUGCCACUCGGCUGUGGACCCUGCUGAGUAUUACAAGAGGUGCAAAUAUGACACGUGUAACUGUCAGAACAAUGAGGACUGCCUGUGCGCCGCCCUGUCCUCCUACGCGCGCGCCUGCACCGCCAAGGGCGUCAUGCUGUGGGGCUGGCGGGAGCAUGUCUGCAACAAGGAUGUGGGCUCCUGCCCCAACUCGCAGGUCUUCCUGUACAACCUGACCACCUGCCAGCAGACCUGCCGCUCCCUCUCCGAGGCCGACAGCCACUGUCUCGAGGGCUUUGCGCCUGUGGACGGCUGCGGCUGCCCUGACCACACCUUCCUGGACGAGAAGGGCCGCUGCGUACCCCUGGCCAAGUGCUCCUGUUACCACCGCGGUCUCUACCUGGAGGCGGGGGACGUGGUCGUCAGGCAGGAAGAACGAUGUGUGUGCCGGGAUGGGCGGCUGCACUGUAGGCAGAUCCGGCUGAUCGGCCAGAGCUGCACGGCCCCAAAGAUCCACAUGGACUGCAGCAACCUGACUGCACUGGCCACCUCGAAGCCCCGAGCCCUCAGCUGCCAGACGCUGGCCGCCGGCUAUUACCACACAGAGUGUGUCAGUGGCUGUGUGUGCCCCGACGGGCUGAUGGAUGACGGCCGGGGUGGCUGCGUGGUGGAGAAGGAAUGCCCUUGCGUCCAUAACAACGACCUGUAUUCUUCCGGCGCCAAGAUCAAGGUGGACUGCAAUACCUGCACCUGCAAGAGAGGACGCUGGGUGUGCACCCAGGCUGUGUGCCAUGGCACCUGCUCCAUUUACGGGAGUGGCCACUACAUCACCUUUGACGGGAAGUACUACGACUUUGACGGACACUGCUCCUACGUGGCUGUUCAGGACUACUGCGGCCAGAACUCCUCACUGGGCUCAUUCAGCAUCAUCACCGAGAACGUCCCCUGUGGCACUACGGGCGUCACCUGCUCCAAGGCCAUCAAGAUCUUCAUGGGGAGGACGGAGCUGAAGUUGGAAGACAAGCACCGUGUGGUGAUCCAGCGUGAUGAGGGUCACCACGUGGCCUACACCACGCGGGAGGUGGGCCAGUACCUGGUGGUGGAGUCCAGCACGGGCAUCAUCGUCAUCUGGGACAAGAGGACCACCGUGUUCAUCAAGCUGGCUCCCUCCUACAAGGGCACCGUGUGUGGCCUGUGUGGGAACUUUGACCACCGCUCCAACAACGACUUCACCACGCGGGACCACAUGGUGGUGAGCAGCGAGCUGGACUUCGGGAACAGCUGGAAGGAGGCCCCCACCUGCCCAGAUGUGAGCACCAACCCCGAGCCCUGCAGCCUGAACCCGCACCGCCGCUCCUGGGCCGAGAAGCAGUGCAGCAUCCUCAAAAGCAGCGUGUUCAGCAUCUGCCACAGCAAGGUGGACCCCAAGCCCUUCUACGAGGCCUGUGUGCACGACUCGUGCUCCUGUGACACGGGUGGGGACUGUGAGUGCUUCUGCUCUGCCGUGGCCUCCUACGCCCAGGAGUGUACCAAAGAGGGGGCCUGCGUGUUCUGGAGGACGCCGGACCUGUGCCCCAUAUUCUGCGACUACUACAACCCUCCGCAUGAGUGUGAGUGGCACUAUGAGCCAUGUGGGAACCGGAGCUUCGAGACCUGCAGGACCAUCAAUGGCAUCCACUCCAACAUCUCCGUGUCCUACCUGGAGGGCUGCUACCCCCGGUGCCCCAAGGACAGGCCCAUCUAUGAGGAGGAUCUGAAGAAGUGUGUCACUGCAGACAAGUGUGGCUGCUAUGUCGAGGACACCCACUACCCACCUGGAGCAUCGGUUCCCACCGAGGAGACCUGCAAGUCCUGCGUGUGUACCAACUCCUCCCAAGUCGUCUGCAGGCCGGAGGAAGGAAAGAUUCUUAACCAGACCCAGGAUGGCGCCUUCUGCUACUGGGAGAUCUGUGGCCCCAACGGGACGGUGGAGAAGCACUUCAACAUCUGUUCCAUUACGACACGCCCGUCCACCCUGACCACCUUCACCACCAUCACCCUCCCCACCACCCCCACCACCUUCACCACUACCACCACCACCACCACCCCGACCUCCAGCACAGUUUUAUCAACAACUCCGAAGCUGUGCUGCCUCUGGUCUGACUGGAUCAAUGAGGACCACCCCAGCAGUGGCAGCGACGACGGUGACCGAGAAACAUUUGAUGGGGUCUGCGGGGCCCCUGAGGACAUCGAGUGCAGGUCGGUCAAGGAUCCCCACCUCAGCUUGGAGCAGCUAGGCCAGAAGGUGCAGUGUGAUGUCUCUGUUGGGUUCAUUUGCAAGAAUGAAGACCAGUUUGGAAAUGGACCAUUUGGACUGUGUUACGACUACAAGAUACGUGUCAAUUGUUGCUGGCCCAUGGAUAAGUGUAUCACCACUCCCAGCCCUCCAACUACCACUCCCAGCCCUCCACCAACCAGCACGACCACCCUUCCACCAACCACCACCCCCAGCCCUCCAACCACCACCACAACCACCCCUCCACCAACCACCACCCCCAGCCCUCCAAUAACCACCACGACCACCCCUCCACCAACCACCACUCCCAGCCCUCCAAUAAGCACCACAACCACCCCUCCACCAACCACCACUCCCAGCCCUCCAACCACCACUCCCAGCCCUCCAACCACCACUCCCAGCCCUCCAACAACCACCACAACCACCCCUCCACCAACCACCACUCCCAGCCCUCCAACGACUACGCCCAUCACUCCACCAGCCAGCACUACCACCCUUCCACCAACCACCACUCCCAGCCCUCCAACAACCACCACAACCACCCCUCCACCAACCACCACUCCCAGUCCUCCAACGACUACGCCCAUCACUCCACCAACCAGCACUACUACCCUUCCACCAACCACCACUCCCAGCCCUCCACCAACCACCACAACCACCCCUCCACCAACCACCACUCCCAGCCCUCCAACAACCACCACUCCCAGUCCUCCAACAAUCACCACAACCACCCCUCCACCAACCACCACUCCCAGCCCUCCAACAACCACCACGACCACCCUUCCACCAACCACCACUUCCAGCCCUCUAACAACUACUCCUCUACCUCCAUCAAUAACUCCUCCUACAUUUUCACCAUUCUCAACGACAACCCCUACUACCCCAUGCGUGCCUCUCUGCAAUUGGACUGGCUGGCUGGAUUCUGGAAAACCCAACUUUCACAAACCAGGUGGAGACACAGAAUUGAUUGGAGACGUCUGUGGACCAGGCUGGGCAGCUAACAUCUCUUGCAGAGCCACCAUGUAUCCUGAUGUUCCCAUUGGACAGCUUGGACAAACAGUGGUGUGUGAUGUCUCUGUGGGGCUGAUAUGCAAAAAUGAAGACCAAAAGCCAGGUGGGGUCAUCCCUAUGGCCUUCUGCCUCAACUACGAGAUCAACGUUCAGUGCUGUGAGUGUGUCACCCAACCCACCACCAUGACAACCACCACCACAGAGAACCCAACUCCGACACCAAUCACCACCACCACUACGGUGACCCCAACCCCAACACCCACCAGCACACAGAGUACAACACCAACACCCAUCACCACCACCAAUACGGUAACCCCAACCCCAACCCCCACUGGCACACAGACCCCAACCCCGACACCCAUCACCACCACCACCACUAUGGUGACCCCAACACCAACAAUCACCAGCACACAGACCCCAACCCCGACACCCAUCACCACCACUACGGUGACCCCAACCCCAACACCCACCAGCACACAGAGAACAACACCGACAUCCAUCACCACCACCACCACGGUGACCCCAACCCCAACACCCACCGGCACACAGACCCCAACCACGACACCCAUCACCACCACCACCACGGUGACCCCAACCCCAACACCCACCGGCACACAGACCCCAACAACGACACCCAUCACCACCACCACCAUGGUGACCCCAACCCCAACACCCACUGGAACACAGACCCAAACCCCAACACCCAUCACCACCACCACUACGGUGACCCCAACCCCUACACCCACCGGCACACAGACCCCAACAUCGACACCCAUCAGCACCACCACUACGGUGACCCCAACACCAACACCCACCGGCACACAGACCCCAACCCUGACACCCAUCACCACCACCACUACGGUGACCCCAACCCCAACACCCACCGGCACACAGACCCCAACCACGACACCCAUCACCACCACCACUACGGUGACCCCAACCCCAACACCCACCGGCACAAAGAGUACAACCCCGACAUCCAUCACCACCACCACUAUGGUGACCCCAACCCCACCACCCACUGGCACACAGACCCCAACCACGACACCCAUCACCACCACCACUACGGUGACCCCAACCCCAACACCCACCGGCACACAGACCCCAACCCCGACACCCAUCACCACCACCACCACGGUGACCCCAACCCCAACACCCACCGGCACACAGACCCCAACAUCGACACCCAUCACCACCAACACUACGGUGACCCCAACCCCAACACCAACCGGCACACCGAGUACAACCCUGACACCCAUCACCACCACCACUAUGGUGACCCCAACCCCAACACCCACCGGCACACAGACCCCAACAUCGACACCCAUCAGCACCACCACUACGGUGACCCCAACCUCAACACCCACCGGCACACAGACCCCAACCCCGACACCCAUCUCCACCACCACUACGGUGACCCCAACCCCGACACCCAUCUCCACCACCACUACAGUGACCCCAACCCCAACACCCACCGGCACACAGACCCCAACCAUGACACCCAUCACCACCACCACCACGGUGACCCCAACCCCAACACCCACCGGCACACAGACCCCAACAACGACACCCAUCAGCACCACCACCACAGUGACCCCAACCCCAACACCCACCGGCACACAGACCCCAACAUCGACACCCAUCACCACCACCACUACGGUGACCCCAACCCCAACACCCACCGGCACACAGACCCCAACCACGACACCCAUCACCACCACCACCACGGUGACCCCAACCCCAACACCCACCGGCACACAGAGUACAACCCUGACACCCAUCACCACCACCACCACGGUGACACCAACCCCAACACCCACCGGCACACAGACCCCAACCCCGACACCCAUCUCCACCACCACUACGGUGACCCCAACCCCAACACCCACCGGCACACAGACCCCAACCACGACACCCAUCACCACCACCACCACGGUGACCCCAACCCCAACACCCACCGGCACACAGACCCCAACAACGACACCCAUCAGCACCACCACCACGGUGACCCCAACCCCAACACCCACCGGCACACAGACCCCAACAUCGACACCCAUCACCACCACCACUACGGUGACCCCAACCCCAACACCCACCGGCACACAGACCCCAACCACGACACCCAUCACCACCACCACCACGGUGACCCCAACCCCAACACCCACUGGCACACAGGCCCCAACCCCAACAGCCAUCACCACCACCACUACGGUGACCCCAACCCCAACACCCACCGGCACACAGACCCCAACAACGACACCCAUCACCACCACCACCAUGGUGACCCCAACCCCAACACCCACCGGCACACAGACCCCAACAUCGACACCCAUCACCACCACCACUACGGUGACCCCAACCCCAACACCCACCGGCACACAGACCCCAACCCCGACACCCAUCUCCACCACCACUACGGUGACCCCAACCCCAACACCCACCGGCACACAGACCCCAACCAUGACACCCAUCACCACCACCACCACGGUGACCCCAACCCCAACACCCACCGGCACACAGACCCCAACAACGACACCCAUCAGCACCACCACCACGGUGACCCCAACCCCAACACCCACCGGCACACAGACCCCAACAUCGACACCCAUCACCACCACCACUACGGUGACCCCAACCCCAACACCCACCGGCACACAGACCCCAACCCCGACACCCAUCACCACCACCACCACGGUGACCCCAACCCCAACACCCACCGGCACACAGACCCCAACAUCGACACCCAUCACCACCACCACUACGGUGACCCCAACCCCAACACCCACCGGCACACAGACCCCAACCACGACACCCAUCACCACCACCACCACGGUGACCCCAACCCCAACACCCACCGGCACACAGAGUACAACCCUGACACCCAUCACCACCACCACCACGGUGACACCAACCCCAACACCCACCGGCACACAAAACCCAACAUCAACACCCAUCACCACCACCACUACGGUGACCCCAACCCCAAAACCCACCGGCACACAGACCCCAACCCCAACACCCAUCUCCACCACCAAUAAGGUGACCCCAACCCCAACACCCACCGGCACACAGACCCCAACCAUGACACCCAUCACCACCACCACCACGGUGACCCCAACCCCAACACCCACCGGCACACAGACCCCAACAUCGACACCCAUCACCACCACCACUACGGUGACCCCAACCCCAACACCCACCGGCACACAGACCCCAACCAUGACACCCAUCACCACCACCACCACGGUGACCCCAACCCCAACACCCACUGGCACACAGGCCCCAACCCCAACAGCCAUCACCACCACCACUACGGUGACCCCAACCCCAACACCCACCGGCACACAGACCCCAACCACGACACCCAUCACCACCACCACCACGGUGACCCCAACCCCAACACCCACCGGCACACAGAGUACAACCCUGACACCCAUCACCACCACCACCACGGUGACACCAACCCCAACACCCACCGGCACACAGACCCCAACCCCGACACCCAUCUCCACCACCACUACGGUGACCCCAACCCCAACACCCACCGGCACACAGACCCCAACCAUGACACCCAUCACCACCACCACCACGGUGACCCCAACCCCAACACCCACCGGCACACAGACCCCAACAACGACACCCAUCAGCACCACCACCACGGUGACCCCAACCCCAACACCCACCGGCACACAGACCCCAACAUCGACACCCAUCACCACCACCACUACGGUGACCCCAACCCCAACACCCACCGGCACACAGACCCCAACCACGACACCCAUCACCACCACCACCACGGUGACCCCAACCCCAACACCCACUGGCACACAGGCCCCAACCCCAACAGCCAUCACCACCACCAGUACGGUGACCCCAACCCCAACACCCACCGGCACACAGACCCCAACCACGACACCCAUCACCACCACCACUACGGUGACACCAACCCCAACACCCACCGGCACACAGUCCCCAACCCCAACAGCCAUCACCACCACCACUACGGUGACCCCAACCCCAACACCCACCGGCACACAGACCCCAACAUUGACGCCCAUCACCACCACCACUACGGUGACCCCAACCCCAACACCCACCGGCACACAGACCCCAACCCCGACACCCAUCUCCACCACCACUACGGUGACCCCAACCCCAACACCCACCGGCACACAGACCCCAACCACGACACCCAUCACCACCACCACCACGGUGACCCCAACCCCGACACCCACCGGCACACAGACCCCAACCACGGUACUCAUCACCACCACCACUACGAUGACCCCAACCCCAACACCCACCAGCACAAAGAGUACAACCGUGACACCCAUCACCACCACAACUACGGUGACCGCAACCCCAACACCCACCGGCACACAGACCCCAACCAUGAUACCCAUCAGCACCACCACUACGGUGACCCCAACCCCAACACCCACCACUGGAAGCACGGGGCCCCCCACCCACACAAGCACAGCACCGAUUGCUGAGUUGACCACAUCCAAUCCUCCGCCUGAGUCCUCAACCCCUCAGACCUCUCGGUCCACCUCUUCCCCUCUCACGGAGUCAACCACCCUUCUGAGUACCCUACCACCUGCCAUUGAGAUGACCAGCACGGCCCCACCCUCCACACCCACGGCACCCACGACCACGAGCGGAGGCCACACACUGUCUCCACCGCCCAGCACCACCACGUCCCCUCCAGGCACCCCCACUCGCGGUACCACGACUGGGUCAUCUUCAGCCCCCACCCCCAGCACUGUGCAGACGACCACCACCAGUGCCUGGACCCCCACGCCGACCCCACUCUCCACACCCAGCAUCAUCAGGACCACAGGCCUGAGGCCCUACCCUUCCUCUGUGCUUAUCUGCUGUGUCCUGAACGACACCUACUACGCACCAGGUGAGGAGGUGUACAACGGCACAUACGGAGACACCUGUUAUUUCGUCAACUGCUCACUGAGCUGUACGUUGGAGUUCUAUAACUGGUCCUGCCCAUCCACGCCCUCCCCAACACCCACGCCCUCCAAGUCGACGCCCACGCCUUCCAAGCCAUCGUCCACGCCCUCCAAGCCGACGCCCGGCACCAAGCCCCCCGAGUGCCCAGACUUUGAUCCUCCCAGACAGGAGAACGAGACUUGGUGGCUGUGCGACUGCUUCAUGGCCACGUGCAAGUACAACAACACGGUGGAGAUCGUGAAGGUGGAGUGUGAGCCGCCGCCCAUGCCCACCUGCUCCAACGGCCUCCAACCCGUGCGCGUCGAGGACCCCGACGGCUGCUGCUGGCACUGGGAGUGCGACUGCUACUGCACGGGCUGGGGCGACCCGCACUAUGUCACCUUCGACGGACUCUACUACAGCUACCAGGGCAACUGCACCUACGUGCUGGUGGAGGAGAUCAGCCCCUCCGUGGACAACUUCGGAGUUUACAUCGACAACUACCACUGCGAUCCCAACGACAAGGUGUCCUGCCCCCGCACCCUCAUCGUGCGCCACGAGACCCAGGAGGUGCUGAUCAAGACCGUGCAUAUGAUGCCCAUGCAGGUGCAGGUGCAGGUGAACAGGCAGGCGGUGGCACUGCCCUACAAGAAGUACGGGCUGGAGGUGUACCAGUCUGGCAUCAACUACGUGGUGGACAUCCCCGAGCUGGGUGUCCUCGUCUCCUACAAUGGCCUGUCCUUCUCCGUCAGGCUGCCCUACCACCGGUUUGGCAACAACACCAAGGGCCAGUGUGGCACCUGCACCAACACCACCUCCGACGACUGCAUUCUGCCCAGCGGGGAGAUCGUCUCCAACUGUGAGGCUGCGGCUGACCAGUGGCUGGUGAACGACCCCUCCAAGCCACACUGCCCCCACAGCAGCUCCACGACCAAGCGCCCGGCCGUCACUGUGCCCGGGGGCGGUAAAACGACCCCACACAAGGACUGCACCCCAUCUCCCCUCUGCCAGCUCAUCAAGGACAGCCUGUUUGCCCAGUGCCACGCACUGGUGCCCCCGCAGCACUACUACGAUGCCUGCGUGUUCGACAGCUGCUUCAUGCCGGGCUCGAGCCUGGAGUGCGCCAGUCUGCAGGCCUACGCAGCCCUCUGUGCCCAGCAGAACAUCUGCCUCGACUGGCGGAACCACACGCAUGGGGCCUGCUUGGUGGAGUGCCCAUCUCACAGGGAGUACCAGGCCUGUGGCCCUGCAGAAGAGCCCACGUGCAAAUCCAGCUCCUCCCAGCAGAACAACACAGUCCUGGUGGAAGGCUGCUUCUGUCCUGAGGGCACCAUGAACUACGCUCCUGGCUUUGAUGUCUGCGUGAAGACCUGCGGCUGUGUGGGACCUGACAAUGUGCCCAGAGAGUUUGGGGAGCACUUCGAGUUCGACUGCAAGAACUGUGUCUGCCUGGAGGGUGGAAGUGGCAUCAUCUGCCAACCCAAGAGGUGCAGCCAGAAGCCCGUUACCCACUGCGUGGAAGACGGCACCUACCUCGCCACGGAGGUCAACCCUGCCGACACCUGCUGCAACAUUACCGUCUGCAAGUGCAACACCAGCCUGUGCAAAGAGAAGCCCUCCGUGUGCCCGCUGGGAUUCGAAGUGAAGAGCAAGAUGGUGCCUGGAAGGUGCUGUCCUUUCUACUGGUGUGAGUCCAAGGGGGUGUGUGUUCACGGGAAUGCUGAGUACCAGCCCGGUUCUCCAGUUUAUUCCUCCAAGUGCCAGGACUGCGUGUGCACGGACAAGGUGGACAACAACACCCUGCUCAACGUCAUCGCCUGCACCCACGUGCCCUGCAACACCUCCUGCAGCCCUGGCUUCGAACUCAUGGAGGCCCCCGGGGAGUGCUGUAAGAAGUGUGAACAGACGCACUGUAUCAUCAAACGGCCCGACAACCAGCACGUCAUCCUGAAGCCCGGGGACUUCAAGAGCGACCCGAAGAACAACUGCACAUUCUUCAGCUGCGUGAAGAUCCACAACCAGCUCAUCUCGUCCGUCUCCAACAUCACCUGCCCCAACUUUGAUGCCAGCAUUUGCAUCCCGGGCUCCAUCACAUUCAUGCCCAAUGGAUGCUGCAAGACCUGCACCCCUCGCAAUGAGACCAGGGUGCCCUGCUCCACCGUCCCCGUCACCACGGAGGUUUCGUACGCCGGCUGCACCAAGACCGUCCUCAUGAAUCAUUGCUCCGGGUCCUGCGGGACAUUUGUCAUGUACUCGGCCAAGGCCCAGGCCCUGGACCACAGCUGCUCCUGCUGCAAAGAGGAGAAAACCAGCCAGCGUGAGGUGGUCCUGAGCUGCCCCAAUGGCGGCUCGCUGACACACACCUACACCCACAUCGAGAGCUGCCAGUGCCAGGACACCGUCUGCGGGCUCCCCACCGGCACCUCCCGCCGGGCCCGGCGCUCCCCUAGGCAUCUGGGGAGCGGGUGAGCGGGGUGGGCACAGCCCCCUUCACUGCCCUCGACAGCUUUACCUCCCCCGGACCCUCUGAGCCUCCUAAGCUCGGCUUCCUCUCUUCAGAUAUUUAUUGUCUGAGUCUUUGUUCAGUCCUUGCUUUCCAAUAAUAAACUCAGGGGGACAUGC